AGGAAGCUGCGAGCGCGCUGGGGAGCGCAGCUGCAGGCGUUGGGGCGGCAGGAGCCGCGGAGCCGGCGCUGAGAGGGGCUGCGGCCGGAGCGGGCGGCUGAGACAAAGGCGACGAUAGGGCCAGAUUUGAGUGUGUGAAUUUUUGAGUGAAACCUGGAACCCAAAUGAGAAGAAAUCUGCAAGGAAUAACUACUGACAGUGAAUCUGCGGUCAUCUGUAUGCAUAAUAUGGAAUGUUCUUAACCCAGAAGUAGCUGAAUGUGUUACUCCAUUGCUGAGGAGUGACUAUCUGUUAUAGUCCCUGGGUCAAGACAACAAUUUUUAUACCUUCGUCGUGGUUCAGAAAGGAGUCUCUGUAGAACCAGAAGCAAAGAAAGGAAACAAUCCAAAUUUUUCUUUAUUAAAUCGACUGUGUAAGAUACUUGACUUCCAGGAACAAAAACACGGUGAAAUAAUAAAAUUUCAUCUUGGCAUCACUGGACAUCAUCGUAUUGAGGAGCGUAUUUUUGGAACUUCCCGAGUUGAGAUUUGGAACCUUCAUUGGUGCUCAUUUACUGUGGACUGUAAGCAUGAGUGAAUUCUGGUUGUGUUUCAACUGCUGUAUUGCAGAACAGCCUCAGCCUAAAAGGCGACGGCGGAUUGACAGAAGUAUGAUUGGAGAGCCCACAAACUUUGUGCAUACAGCUCAUGUUGGAUCAGGAGACCUGUUCAGUGGAAUGAAUUCAGUUAGCUCCAUUCAGAACCAAAUGCAGUCCAAGGGAGGUUAUGGAGGUGGAAUGCCUGCCAAUGUCCAGAUGCAGCUCGUGGAUACGAAGGCGGGAUAGCCCUGGUCCUUUCUCCAGUGAGUACUCAGAGCUGGGGUCUGGACCUGACGGCCAGACAUGGCCAGGCCAAUAAUAGUAAAUAUAUGUAUAUAUAUAUAAUUUUUUAAUGGUGAACUUAUUGGGAAAGGCAAAAUUACUCAGCUAAGUGUAGUUUCUGCACUUGGAAUGUAAGUUUUAGGUUCUUUUCCUUAUUAAGAACUUUAAAUACUUUAAAACAUCUGGUUGGGGAGGAUUCUGAUGACAAGAUGCUUCUUAUGUGUCCUUUAAACAAGAGUGAAAUCAUUAUUUUGAGUAUUGAGGCCGAGCAUGGUGGCUCACACCUGUAAUCCCAGCACUUUGGGAGGCCUAGGUGGGCUGAUCACCUGAGGCCAGGAAUUGGAGACUAGCCUGGCCAACAUGGUGAAACCCCAUCUCUACUAAAAAUACAAAAAUUAGCUGGGCAUGGUGGCGCAUGCCUGUAAUCGCAGCUACUCAGGAGGCUGAGGCACGAGAAUUGCUUGAACCUGGGAGGCAGGGGUUGCAGUCAGCUGAGAAUGCGCCACUGCGCUCCAGCCUGGGUGACAGAGCAAGACCCUGUCUCAAAAAAGUACUGAUACUAAAGAUAAUCUCUUGGGUAGUAAUUUUACAGUUAAGACUUCAUUGUUUAUAAACUUUUCAAAUUAAUUAAAAAGACUACUUUGAAAAAGGAUAAACCCUGAAAAUGUAGAAAUAAUUUCAAGUUUUUUUUUGUUUUAUAGGGUUAUUGUGAAUUUCUAUAUUUUCUCUGUCCACUAUUCUGUAAUUUUUUUUUGUCCUGUGAUUGCUUUUAUUUUGAAUUACAAAAAAGAAGUGUGAUGGCACCUUGUCCACCCUGUCGUGAUUAUUCCAGUGAGAUGUUACUGUUCUGCUCUGAAGAAGAUACUGUCAGACGAAUCCUGCAUUUCCUUCAGCUGGCAUGCAUGCCUUUGGACUCAUGGACAGAGUUCUUUGGAUUGUCACUGAAUUUUCAAUGUUUAAUCAGUAUGGAUCUGAUCUUCGCAUGAUCUUUUUUGUGAAUGCUAACACCAUUUUGCAGUUUUUUUUUUCUAUUUUAAACAUUUUUCUUUUCACUGCCGACCCCCUGCCUUACGAUUUUAUUGGAAAGCAAGGACCUGCUAUUAUUUGUUAAUUUGCCAUCAUUUAUGUAUAUUUUGGAAGGUAUGAGACCCACAAGCACAAUGAUCAUUUUUAUUUGUUUGUUUGUUUGAAACUUCAGCAGAAUAGAUAUCUGCAUGCUUUAUGAAGUUGUUGCUUCGGUAAGAGCCCAUGGGAUGCCAGAAAUUAACAUUUCUUUGCUGCCAUGGGCUGAUGAUGCUGCUAUUAGAUAAAGUUUAGCUGUGGCACCAAGUCACAUCAUUUUCAUAGAAAAAGAUUACUUGUAGCUUAUUUUAGAAGUAUGACCUUUUGGUCUGUUUGAUUGAUUGAUUAGAAUUGCAAUAAAAGAAAAGCUUGCAUUCAUAAGGCAUUCAUUCUGUUGUAAAUGUUCAAUAUAUUUAUUUUGAGAGCAAGGACCUGUGGUUGUAAACAGGUGUGGUUACAGGUGUGGUUAUGUAUCUGAGUGUUGCGGUCAUACUCUCCUCCAGUCCAAUCCUGAGCAUCUUCAUCUUAUUAAUUAGCUGUUCGUUUCUUUGUGCACUCAUUCUUUUAUUUUUACUUCUUUUUAAUGUUAUGGUAUCCAGUUGUUUCCAGUAGCAGUUUCUUGAACUUCUGGCCUGUACUACUAACUGCAGACCUCCAGAGUCACUGGCCUUUCUGUGCUCUACAUAUUAUUUUAGGGGCCACAUCAGUUGCCAAGAGCAACAUACAUACCGACCUGGCUGAAUUAUUGCCAGUGAAAACAACCUGUACGAAGCCUUUGCUCAGGUUCUAAAAUAUGUUUGUCCUUGCACGAAUUUUGUAUAUUUCAAAUAUUUCUGUAAAGGUUUCUUCUUUUCUGUUAGAGUGUGGUGUUAAGCCAGAGUCAGUGGUUUGUGUUCUCAUUAAAAUGUUUGUUUAAAUCCUAUGUCCAAUUCAAGCCUAUCUAACUACAUUUGGUAGGAUUAACAUUUCAUAUAACAAAUGGGGCUUAAUUAAAAACUUUAACUUGGAAUAAAGGAACAGGGAUCACUUUAUCUUCUGCCUUCAUUUACCUUAGUCCAAGAUUCUUGCAAAACAGGCAACUGAACAAACAUUAGGUUUAUGUAGGUAAAAUGUGAAAGCAUUUCUCCUCCACUUUUUAAAAUUUAAUUUACCCAGUACAGCGGGGCACCAGAUUACUUGAUCUUUGUAUUUUGCAGUUUUGAGCCUUUGUGUCAAUCCCAAGCACAGAGAGGAUCUGCCAAGGAAAAACAUUUGCAUCUUCGGAGUAGACAUUUUGCAGUUUGUUUAAUAACAACUUCUAAAGUAAGUUGAAUUCAUCCAUUGUCACUGAUUCACCAAGUGGAUGUUGCAUUGUGGAAUUUGCCUGAGUACUGUUGUCAUUCUGCUCAGCCAGGCACGGUCAGUUUCUUGGCCAGGGACAUUGCUAUGUGCUGUGUGCAAGCUCUUUAGAAGAGAGAUUGGAUUUUCUUGGCAUUAUCAGCACUCAUGCUAUUUAGUCUACUUCUAUUUUGACUGACUCUUUAAAUUAGUACAAUUUUUCUACUUGUCAUAUAACUCCUGGAACAAUAGUACGGGAAGCCGUGAUCCUUUUCCCUGACUCAUGAUUUUAGUCUUUUUCCAAAUCGCUGUUUUUUUUUUUUUUUUUUUUUUUUUUGCUGCUCCAACGACCAGCAUGUGUUGGAGCAGAUCUCCAUGGUAAGCCAAAAGUGGACUUGUCAGCCUAUAACUACUCUGCAGCUGCCACUAACUCUACAGGCACAGUAACUACACUUUAUACAGGAGCACAUGCCAAAGUGCCUGGGAGGUGCCAAUAAAAUCAAGAAAUAAGAAAACUACAAAAAAAGAUACGGUAUUAACCUUGGACAUAAUUUUUUUUAGGGAGGCAGCUUUCCCACUUUUAUAAAGGGGGUUGUAAAUCUCAAGAGGUCAUUUGUUCCCCAUAGCAGCAUAUCUCAUUUUUAAAUUGAAGCGAAUUAAAUAGGAUUUUACUACUCAACAUUCAUUAUACUGUUAAUCUUUGCUGAAAUAUAUGCUAACAAAUGUUAAGCAAGGGAAACUGAAGACUUAGUCAUGUGGAUUGUUAGCAGUGAUCUGCAUUCUGUAAAAGAGGUACUUUCCCAUGAUGUAGGCAUGAAGUGGUGCCAGUAAGCGUAGAGCGGAAAUGUUGACUUUAGUUAACAUUGGGUUUAGCAUUUCCAGUGCAGCAUUAUCAGUGGGCCUUUAAAAAUACUUCGUAAGUACAUUAGCUUUCACUUUGUUGUUAAAUUAUAGCAGACUCAUUAUAGAGAACAAGUUUGCCUUGAUUUUGUUUAAAAUGACUUCUGCUAAGCACCCAGAAGAUAAAAUUGACAUAUUUUUAUAAUAUAAGCAUACUUUUUUUGUACAUUGUGUUCAUUCUUGAAUAAAAUGAGUUCUGUGUUGGCUUGUAGAUACUAAAAAGAAAGUAUUGAUUUUGAUUCAAUAAAUGUUUUCUUUCAAUCCUG